AGUCCCGCGACCGAAGCAGGGCGCGCAGCAGCGCUGAGUGCCCCGGAACGUGCGUCGCGCCCCCAGUGUCCGUCGCGUCCGCCGCGCCCCGGGCGGGGAUGGGGCGGCCAGACUGAGCGCCGCACCCGCCAUCCAGACCCGCCGGCCCUAGCCGCAGUCCCUCCAGCCGUGGCCCCAGCGCGCACGGGCGAUGGCGAAGGCGACGUCCGGUGCCGCGGGGCUGCGUCUGCUGUUGCUGCUGCUGCUGCCGCUGCUAGGCAAAGUGGCAUUGGGCCUCUACUUCUCGAGGGAUGCUUACUGGGAGAAGCUGUAUGUGGACCAGGCAGCCGGCACGCCCUUGCUGUACGUCCAUGCCCUGCGGGACGCCCCUGAGGAGGUGCCCAGCUUCCGCCUGGGCCAGCAUCUCUACGGCACGUACCGCACACGGCUGCAUGAGAACAACUGGAUCUGCAUCCAGGAGGACACCGGCCUCCUCUACCUUAACCGGAGCCUGGACCAUAGCUCCUGGGAGAAGCUCAGUGUCCGCAACCGCGGCUUUCCCCUGCUCACCGUCUACCUCAAGGUCUUCCUGUCACCCACAUCCCUUCGUGAGGGCGAGUGCCAGUGGCCAGGCUGUGCCCGCGUAUACUUCUCCUUCUUCAACACCUCCUUUCCAGCCUGCAGCUCCCUCAAGCCCCGGGAGCUCUGCUUCCCAGAGACAAGGCCCUCCUUCCGCAUUCGGGAGAACCGACCCCCAGGCACCUUCCACCAGUUCCGCCUGCUGCCUGUGCAGUUCUUGUGCCCCAACAUCAGCGUGGCCUACAGGCUCCUGGAGGGUGAGGGUCUGCCCUUCCGCUGCGCCCCGGACAGCCUGGAGGUGAGCACGCGCUGGGCCCUGGACCGCGAGCAGCGGGAGAAGUACGAGCUGGUGGCCGUGUGCACCGUGCACGCCGGCGCGCGCGAGGAGGUGGUGAUGGUGCCCUUCCCGGUGACCGUGUACGACGAGGACGACUCGGCGCCCACCUUCCCCGCGGGCGUCGACACCGCCAGCGCCGUGGUGGAGUUCAAGCGGAAGGAGGACACCGUGGUGGCCACGCUGCGUGUCUUCGAUGCAGACGUGGUACCUGCAUCAGGGGAGCUGGUGAGGCGGUACACAAGCACGCUGCUCCCCGGGGACACCUGGGCCCAGCAGACCUUCCGGGUGGAACACUGGCCCAACGAGACCUCGGUCCAGGCCAACGGCAGCUUCGUGCGGGCGACCGUACAUGACUAUAGGCUGGUUCUCAACCGGAACCUCUCCAUCUCGGAGAACCGCACCAUGCAGCUGGCGGUGCUGGUCAAUGACUCAGACUUCCAGGGCCCAGGAGCGGGCGUCCUCUUGCUCCACUUCAACGUGUCGGUGCUGCCGGUCAGCCUGCACCUGCCCAGUACCUACUCCCUCUCCGUGAGCAGGAGGGCUCGCCGAUUUGCCCAGAUCGGGAAAGUCUGUGUGGAAAACUGCCAGGCAUUCAGUGGCAUCAACGUCCAGUACAAGCUGCAUUCCUCUGGUGCCAACUGCAGCACGCUAGGGGUGGUCACCUCAGCCGAGGACACCUCGGGGAUCCUGUUUGUGAAUGACACCAAGGCCCUGCGGCGGCCCAAGUGUGCCGAACUUCACUACAUGGUGGUGGCCACCGACCAGCAGACCUCUAGGCAGGCCCAGGCCCAGCUGCUUGUAACAGUGGAGGGGUCAUAUGUGGCCGAGGAGGCGGGCUGCCCCCUGUCCUGUGCAGUCAGCAAGAGACGGCUGGAGUGUGAGGAGUGUGGCGGCCUGGGCUCCCCAACAGGCAGGUGUGAGUGGAGGCAAGGAGAUGGCAAAGGGAUCACCAGGAACUUCUCCACCUGCUCUCCCAGCACCAAGACCUGCCCCGACGGCCACUGCGAUGUUGUGGAGACCCAAGACAUCAACAUUUGCCCUCAGGACUGCCUCCGGGGCAGCAUUGUUGGGGGACACGAGCCUGGGGAGCCCCGGGGGAUUAAAGCUGGCUAUGGCACCUGCAACUGCUUCCCUGAGGAGGAGAAGUGCUUCUGCGAGCCCGAAGACAUCCAGGAUCCACUGUGCGACGAGCUGUGCCGCACGGUGAUCGCAGCCGCUGUCCUCUUCUCCUUCAUCGUCUCGGUGCUGCUGUCUGCCUUCUGCAUCCACUGCUACCACAAGUUUGCCCACAAGCCACCCAUCUCCUCAGCUGAGAUGACCUUCCGGAGGCCCGCCCAGGCCUUCCCGGUCAGCUACUCCUCUUCCGGUGCCCGCCGGCCCUCGCUGGACUCCAUGGAGAACCAGGUCUCCGUGGAUGCCUUCAAGAUCCUGGAGGAUCCAAAGUGGGAAUUCCCUCGGAAGAACUUGGUUCUUGGAAAAACUCUAGGAGAAGGCGAAUUUGGAAAAGUGGUCAAGGCAACGGCCUUCCAUCUGAAAGGCAGAGCAGGGUACACCACGGUGGCCGUGAAGAUGCUGAAAGAGAACGCCUCCCCGAGUGAGCUGCGAGACCUGCUGUCAGAGUUCAACGUCCUGAAGCAGGUCAACCACCCACAUGUCAUCAAAUUGUAUGGGGCCUGCAGCCAGGAUGGCCCGCUCCUCCUCAUCGUGGAGUACGCCAAAUACGGCUCCCUGCGGGGCUUCCUCCGCGAGAGCCGCAAAGUGGGGCCUGGCUACCUGGGCAGUGGAGGCAGCCGCAACUCCAGCUCCCUGGACCACCCGGAUGAGCGGGCCCUCACCAUGGGCGACCUCAUCUCAUUUGCCUGGCAGAUCUCACAGGGGAUGCAGUAUCUGGCCGAGAUGAAGCUCGUUCAUCGGGACUUGGCAGCCAGAAACAUCCUGGUAGCUGAGGGGCGGAAGAUGAAGAUUUCGGAUUUCGGCUUGUCCCGAGAUGUUUAUGAAGAGGAUUCCUACGUGAAGAGGAGCCAGGGUCGGAUUCCAGUUAAAUGGAUGGCAAUUGAAUCCCUUUUUGAUCAUAUCUACACCACGCAAAGUGAUGUAUGGUCUUUUGGUGUCCUGCUGUGGGAGAUCGUGACCCUAGGGGGAAACCCCUAUCCUGGGAUUCCUCCUGAGCGGCUCUUCAACCUUCUGAAGACCGGCCACCGGAUGGAGAGGCCAGACAACUGCAGCGAGGAGAUGUACCGCCUGAUGCUGCAAUGCUGGAAGCAGGAGCCGGACAAAAGGCCGGUGUUUGCGGACAUCAGCAAAGACCUGGAGAAGAUGAUGGUUAAGAGGAGAGACUACUUGGACCUUGCGGCGUCCACUCCAUCUGACUCCCUGAUUUAUGACGACGGCCUCUCAGAGGAGGAGACACCGCUGGUGGACUGUAAUAAUGCCCCCCUCCCUCGAGCCCUCCCUUCCACAUGGAUUGAAAACAAACUCUAUGGUAGAAUUUCCCAUGCAUUUACUAGAUUCUAGCACCGCUGUCCCCUUUGCACUAUCCUUCCUCUCUGUGAUGCUUUUUAAAAAUGUUUCUGGUCUGAACAAAACCAAAGUCUGCUCUGAACCUUUUUAUUUGUAAAUGUCUGACUUUGCAUCCAGUUUACAUUUAGGCAUUAUUGCAACUAUGUUUUUCUAAAAGGAUGUGAAAAUAAGUGUAAUUACCACAUUGCCCAGCAACUUAGGAUGGUAGAGGAAAAAACAGAUCAGGGCGGAACUCUCAGGGGAGACCAAGAACAGGUUGAAUAAGGCGCUUCUGGGGUGGGAAUCAAGUCAUAGUACUUCUACUUUAACUAAGUGGAUAAAUAUACAAAUCUGGGGAGGUAUUCAGUUGAGAAAGGAGCCACCAGCACCACUCAGCCUGCACUGGGAGCACAGCCAGGUUCCCCCAGACCCCUCCUGGGCAGGCAGGUGCCUCUCAGAGGCCACCCGGCACUGGCGAGCAGCCACUGGCCAAGCCUCAGCCCCAGUCCCAGCCACAUGUCCUCCAUCAGGGGUAGCGAGGUUGCAGGAGCUGGCUGGCCCUGGGAGGACGCACCCCCACUGCUGUUUUCACAUCCUUUCCCUUACCCACCUUCAGGACGGUUGUCACUUAUGAAGUCAGUGCUAAAGCUGGAGCAGUUGCUUUUUGAAAGAACAUGGUCUGUGGUGCUGUGGUCUUACAAUGGACAGUAAAUAUGGUUCUUGCCAAAACUCCUUCUUUUGUCUUUGAUUAAAUACUAGAAAUUUUUUCUGUUUCCUAACUUCAUCAUUGAUUGUUUGAAAUCUUGGAGUUUCAAGCAUUUUUUUCAAGCUGAGACGGUUCCUUUUGCAUGCCUCCUGACUCACUGACUCCUCACUGGCUUUGUGUCUAGUGCCACACUCCAUUUGUGCUGACGAUGCUAUGAGGCUGGCCCGUGUGCACCCUCGAUUUGGAAGGUCCUCUUCUCCGUUGUAGGCUCAGACAACAGACGAGUGCCUCCUUUACGUUAGAGAAUGUUUUAUAGAACGUUUCCGCUGCAGUAAGCCAUUGAGUGCAGCAGUGUGCUGUUGCCCUACACUGCCUUAGAAAAAGAGUUAAGCAGUUCGACAAAUAUACAUCAGAUUAGAGAGUCUCAAGUUCAUAAAAGUCAAAAUUGGUAGUGUCUGUUAAGUUACAUUUACCAAGAGAGCACAUGAUAUUUCCCCUAACUAUAACAGUGUUUUUGGAAACCUGGAACACAAAACCAUUAAUAUAAUUGGCACAGAAACCACGAGUUUGGUUUGAACAUCAAAGGGAGUUUUGCCAAGGCCUUACUGUCUGCACUUGAAGUUUUGGUUCUUCAGUGCAGAACAAAUGAUCUGUUUUCAUUUUUAGGCAUGUCAGACCCGAACUGGCCUGGAGAGAGUCCUGUACCACUCACGAGAGCUGAUGGCACUAACACUGGGUUUCCAAGAUAUCCAAAUGAUAGUGUAUAUGCUAACUGGAUGCUUUCACCCUCAGCGGCAAAAUUAAUGGACACGUUUGAUAGUUAACAUUUCUUUGUGAAAGGUAAUGGACUCACAAGGGGAAGAAACAUGCUGAGAAUGGAAAGUCUACCGGCCCUUUCUUUGUGAACGUCACAUUGGCCGAGCCGUGUUCAGUUCCCAGGUGGCAGACUCGUUUUUGGUAGUUUGUUUUAACUUCCAAGGUGGUUUUACUUCUGAUAGCCGGUGAUUUUCCCUCCUAGCAGACAUGCCACACCGGGUAAGAGCUCUGAGUCUUAGUGGUUAAGCAUUCCUUUCUCUUCAGUGCCCAGCAGCACCCAGUGUUGGUCUGUGUCCAUCAGUGACCACCAACAUUCUGUGUUCACAUGUGUGGGUCCAACACUUACUACCUGGUGUAUGAAAUUGGACCUGAACUGUUGGAUUUUUCUAGUUGCCGCCAAACAAGGCAAAAAAAUUUAAACAUGAAGCACACACACAAAAAAGGCAGUAGGAAAAAUGCUGGCCCUGAUGACCUGUCCUUAUUCAGAAUGAGAGACUGCGGGGGGGGCCUGGGGGUAGUGUCAAUGCCCCUCCAGGGCUGGAGGGGAAGAGGGGCCCCGAGGAUGGGCCUGGGCUCAGCAUUCGAGAUCUUGAGAAUGAUUUUUUUUAAAUCAUGCAACCUUUCCUUAGGAAGACAUUUGGUUUUCAUCAUGAUUAAGAUGAUUCCUAGAUUUAGCACAAUGGAGAGAUUCCAUGCCAUCUUUACUAUGUGGAUGGUGGUAUCAGGGAAGAGGGCUCACAAGACACAUUUGUCCCCCGGGCCCACCACAUCAUCCUCACGUGUUCGGUACUGAGCAGCCACUACCCCUGAUGAGAACAGUAUGAAGAAAGGGGGCUGUUGGAGUCCCAGAAUUGCUGACAGCAGAGGCUUUGCUGCUGUGAAUCCCACCUGCCACCAGCCUGCAGCACACCCCACAGCCAAGUAGAGGCGAAAGCAGUGGCUCAUCCUACCUGUUAGGAGCAGGUAGGGCUUGUACUCACUUUAAUUUGAAUCUUAUCAACUUACUCAUAAAGGGACAGGCUAGCUAGCUGUGUUAGAAGUAGCAAUGACAAUGACCAAGGACUGCUACACCUCUGAUUACAAUUCUGAUGUGAAAAAGAUGGUGUUUGGCUCUUAUAGAGCCUGUGUGAAAGGCCCAUGGAUCAGCUCUUCCUGUGUUUGUAAUUUAAUGCUGCUACAAGAUGUUUCUGUUUCUUAGAUUCUGACCAUGACUCAUAAGCUUCUUGUCAUUCUUCAUUGCUUGUUUGUGGUCACAGAUGCACAACACUCCUCCAGUCUUGUGGGGGCAGCUUUUGGGAAGUCUCAGCAGCUCUUCUGGCUGUGUUGUCAGCACUGUAACUUCGCAGAAAAGAGUCGGAUUACCAAAACACUGCCUGCUCUUCAGACUUAAAGCACUGAUAGGACUUAAAAUAGUCUCAUUCAAAUACUGUAUUUUAUAUAGGCAUUUCACAAAAACAGCAAAAUUGUGGCAUUUUGUGAGGCCAAGGCUUGGAUGCGUGUGUAAUAGAGCCUUGUGGUGUGUGCGCACACACCCAGAGGGAGAGUUUGAAAAAUGCUUAUUGGACACGUAACCUGGCUCUAAUUUGGGCUGUUUUUCAGAUACACUGUGAUAAGUUCUUUUACAAAUAUCUAUAGACAUGGUAAACUUUUGGUUUUCAGAUAUGCUUAAUGAUAGUCUUACUAAAUGCAGAAAUAAGAAUAAACUUUCUCAAAUUAUUAAAAAUGCCUACACAGUAAGUGUGAAUUGCUGCAACAGGUUUGUUCUCAGGAGGGUAAGAACUCCAGGUCUAAACAGCUGACCCAGUGAUGGGGAAUUUAUCCUUGACCAAUUUAUCCUUGACCAAUAACCUAAUUGUCUAUUCCUGAGUUAUAAAAGUCCCCAUCCUUAUUAGCUCUACUGGAAUUUUCAUACACGUAAAUGCAGAAGUUACUAAGUAUUAAGUAUUACUGAGUAUUAAGUAGUAAUCUGUCAGUUAUUAAAAUUUGUAAAAUCUAUUUAUGAAAGGUCAUUAAACCAGAUCAUGUUCCUUUUUUUGUAAUCAAGGUGACUAAGAAAAUCAGUUGUGUAAAUAAAAUCAUGUAUCAUAAAA